AGUCCAGCCCUUUGUCUAACAAAUGAGGAAACUGAGGCCCCCUAAGCUUGCUAUCGCAAGUGCUCUGUACUUUCCCUACUUAAUCCUCUCAAUCGUUUGAGGCAGGUGAUAGUAAUUCCCUUUUACAGACAAGAAAAGUGAGGCCUGUCGCACCAGAAGAAAAAGGUAUCAGCAGGGAUUUCCGCCCACUCUGCCCAGCUUCAAGGUUCACGGUCGUCCUUCCAUGCACGGCUCUUCCAAGUGUAGCCCUGGGAGCCCGGGGGUCCUUGAGAACCUUUCAGGAAGUCUCUGAGGAACCCAAGACCUUCACUUGGUUGGUGUGAGCACUCCAGGAGGCAGGCACCCUCCCUCAGCCCUCAAGCAAGCAAAAAUGGGUUUAAAAAAAGAAGGAGAAGAAGCAGCAGCAGCAGCCGCCACAGAGCUUGUGACAGCUACAGCCUAAGGGCAACAGGCAGGGGAGACCAAGGACCAGAAAGAGCAGAGGCUUUUUCAAAGAAAGAGAUCCCUCUCCCAGCACCCAGCGAUGGCGGCAAACCCCACCCACAGUGCCUGCUAAGAACAAGUCCCACGUGAGAACAACAUGGCCCCCCGAGAUGCCCACAGGGACCCCGAGAUGCCUGCAGUGCUUGGCUCUCCCGCUGGCCAGCUGCCCACCUGGCUCAGGCCCAGUACUCACCCUGGUCACACCUGGGAGAGGAGGAGAGGAGAGCAUAGCACCUGCAGCAAGAUGGAUGUGGGCAGCAAAGAGGUCCUGAUGGAGAGCCCGCCGGACUACUCCGCAGCUCCCCGGGGCCGAUUUGGCAUUCCCUGCUGCCCAGUGCACCUGAAACGCCUUCUUAUCGUGGUGGUGGUGGUGGUCCUCAUCGUCGUGGUGAUUGUGGGAGCCCUGCUCAUGGGUCUCCACAUGAGCCAGAAACACACGGAGAUGGUUCUGGAGAUGAGCAUUGGGGCGCCGGAAGCCCAGCAACGCCUGGCCCUGAGUGAGCACCUGGUUACCACUGCCACCUUCUCCAUCGGCUCCACUGGCCUCGUGGUGUAUGACUACCAGCAGCUGCUGAUCGCCUACAAGCCAGCCCCUGGCACCUGCUGCUACAUCAUGAAGAUAGCUCCAGAGAGCAUCCCCAGUCUUGAGGCUCUCACUAGAAAAGUCCACAACUUCCAGGCCAAGCCCGCAGUGCCUACGUCUAAGCUGGGCCAGGCAGAGGGGCGAGAUGCAGGCUCAGCACCCUCCGGAGGGGACCCGGCCUUCCUGGGCAUGGCCGUGAGCACCCUGUGUGGCGAGGUGCCGCUCUACUACAUCUAGGACGCCUCCGGUGAGCAGGUGUGAUCCCAGGGCCCCUGAUCAGCAGCGGAGGAGCGCUCGGGCCACCUGCCCGGGCUGUGGAGGAGCGCUCGCGCUGACCAGGCGCUGGGGCGUCCACUGAAGCGGGGUCAUCCAGGCAACUCGGGGGAGGGGAAGCUCACAGACCGGUACUUCCCACUCCCCUGAUUCUCUCUGUCCAUCCUCAACAUUCCUUUGCUUCACAGGGUCAGUGGAAGCCCCAACGGGAAAGGAAACGCCCCGGGCAAAGGGUCUUUUGCAGCUUUUGCAGACGGGCAAGAAGCUGCUUCUGCCCACACCGCAGGGACAAGCCCUGGAGAAAUGGGAGCUUGGGGAGAGGAUGGGAGUGGGCAGAGGUGGCGCCCAGGGGCCCGGGAACUCCUGCCACAACAGAAUAAAGCAGCCUGAUUGAAAAGCAAA